AGGCUCGGCGGGGCGGCGGCACGGACUGACGGAGGGUCGGAAGGACUGAGGGACGGGCGGGCGCACGGCCAGGCCAUGCCUGGGGAGGCUGCCCGCGCCGAGCUGCUGCUGCCCGAGGCGGACCGACCCGGGCCCCGCACAGAUCUGUCCUGCGAUGCGGCCGCUGCCACCACCAUCCUGGGAGGGGACCGGCGGGAGCCCUGUGCUCUGACCCCAGGGCCCAGCCACCUGGCCCUCACGUUCCUGCCCAGCAAGCCGGGUGCCCGGCCCCAGCCCGAGGGAGCCAGCUGGGAUGCAGGGCCUGGUGGGGCACCCUCGGCCUGGGCGGACCCAGGGGAGGGCGGCCCAAGCCCCAUGCUCCUCCCUGAGGGCCUGUCUUCCCAGGCUCUGUCCACGGAGGCUCCUCUCCCGGCCACCCUGGAGCCCCGGAUUGUGAUGGGAGAGGAGACGUGCCAGGCCCUCCUGUCACCCAGAGCUGCCCGGACAGCGCUCAGGGACCAGGAGGGUGGGCACGCAAGCCCAGACCCACCCCCCGAGCUGUGUUCUCAGGGUGAUCUUUCUGUGCCUUCCCCUCCCCCAGACCCUGAUUCCUUCUUCACGCCUCCCUCCACCCCCACCAAGACCACCUAUGCCCUGCUUCCUGCCUGUGGGCCCCACGGGGACGCCAGGGACUCAGAGGCUGAGCUGCGGGAUGAGCUGCUGGACUCGCCCCCCGCCUCACCCUCGGGCUCCUACAUUACGGCCGAUGGGGACAGCUGGGCCUCUUCACCCUCCUGUUCCCUCAGCCUGCUGGCUCCGGCUGAAGGGCUGGACUUCCCCUCAGGCUGGGGCCUGUCCCCGCAGGGGUCCAUGGUGGAUGAACGAGAGCUGCACCCAGCAGGGACCCCAGAGCCCCCGUCCUCUGAGUCCAGCCUCUCUGCAGACAGCAGCUCCUCCUGGGGCCAGGAGGGCCACUUCUUCGACCUGGACUUCCUGGCCAAUGACCCAAUGAUCCCCGCAGCCCUCCUACCCUUCCAGGGCAGCCUCAUCUUUCAGGUGGAGGCAGUGGAGGUGACACCGCUAUCCCCAGAGGAAGAAGAAGAGGAGGCUGUGGCGGAUCCCGACCCAGGUGGGGACCUGGCUGGGGAGGGUGAGGAGGACAGCACGUCUGCCUCCUUCCUGCAGUCACUGUCUGACCUGUCCAUCACGGAGGGCAUGGACGAGGCUUUUGCCUUCCGGGACGACACCUCUGCAGCCUCCUCUGAUUCAGACUCAGCCUCCUACGCAGAGGCAGAUGAUGAGAGGCUGUACAGCGGGGAGCCCCAUGCCCAGGCCACUUUGCUCCAGGACAGUGUCCAGAAGACAGAGGAGGAGAGCGGAGGUGGGGCCAAGGGGCUGCAGGCUCAGGAUGGGACUGUGUCCUGGGCCGUGGAGGCUGCUCCUCAGACCUCAGACAGAGGGGCCUAUCUGUCCCAGAGACAGGAAUUGAUCUCAGAAGUAACAGAAGAGGGCCUUGCUUUAGGCCAGGAGUCCACUGCCACUGUGACCCCUCACACUCUGCAGGUAGCCCCAGGCCUCCAGGUGGAGGUGGCUACCAGAGUGACCCCACAGGCUGGGGAGGAAGAAACAGACUCCACCGCUGGACAAGAAUCUGCUGCCAUGGCAAUGCCUCAGCCCUCCCAGGAGGGCAUCAGCGAGAUCUUAGGCCAAGAGUCUGUCACUGCAGAAAAACUUCCAACUCCACAGGAAGAAACAAGCCUCACAUUGUGUCCAGACUCUCCUCAGAACUUGAAGGAAGAAGGAGGGCUGGACCUCCCCUCUGGCAGAAAGCCUGUAGCUGCAGCCACGAUUGUCCCCAGGCAGGCUAAAGAGGACCUCACCUUACCCCAGGACUCCGCUAUGACACCGCCUCUGCCCCUACAAGACACAGAUCUCUCAUCAGCCCCAAAGCCUGUGGCUGCAGCCACGAUUGUGUCCCAGCAGGCUGAAGAGGGCCUCACCUUACCCCAGGACUCCGUUAUGACACCGCCUCUGCCCCUACAAGACACAGAACUCUCGUCAGCCCCAAAGCCUGUGGCUGCAGCCACGCUUGUGUCCCAGCAGGCUGAAGAGGGCCUCACCUUACCCCAGGACUCCGCUAUGACACCGCCUCUGCCCCUACAAGACACAGAUCUCUCGUCAGCCCCAAAGCCUGUGGCUGCAGCCACGCUUGUGUCCCAGCAGGCUGAAGAGGGCCUCACCUUACCCCAGGACUCCGCUAUGACACCGCCUCUGCCCCUACAAGACACAGAUCUCUCGUCAGCCCCAAAGCCUGUGGCUGCAGCCACGCUUGUGUCCCAGCAGGCUGAAGAGGGCCUCACCUUACCCCAGGACUCCGCUAUGACACCGCCUCUGCCCCUACAAGACACAGAUCUCUCGUCAGCCCCAAAGCCUGUGGCUGCAGCCACGAUUGUGUCCCAGCAGGCUGAAGAGGGCCUCACCUUACCCCAGGACUCCGCUAUGACACCGCCUCUGCCCCUACAAGACACAGAUCUCUCGUCAGCCCCAAAGCCUGUGGCUGCAGCCACGAUUGUGUCCCAGCAGGCUGAAGAGGGCCUCACCUUACCCCAGGACUCCGCUAUGACACCGCCUCUGCCCCUACAAGACACAGAUCUCUCGUCAGCCCCAAAGCCUGUGGCUGCAGCCACGCCUGUGUCCCAGCAGGCUGAAGAGGGCCUCACCUUACCCCAGGACUCCGCUAUGACACCGCCUCUGCCCCUACAAGACACAGAUCUCUCGUCAGCCCCAAAGCCUGUGGCUGCAGCCACGCCUGUGUCCCAGCAGGCUGAAGAGGGCCUCACCUUACCCCAGGACUCCGCUAUGACAGCACCUCUGCCUCUGCAAGACACAGGCCCCACCUCAGGUCCAGAGCCUCUGGCUGUGGCCACCCCUCAAACCUUGCAGGCAGAAGCAGGCUGUGCCCCAGGGACAGAGCCUGUGGCCACCAUGGCUCAGCAGGAAGUAGGUGAGGCCUUAGGCCCCAGGCCAGCACCUGAGGAGAAGAAUGCAGCCCUCCCUACAGUCCCGGAGCCUGCAGCCUUGGACCAGGUCCAACAGGAUGACCCACAGCCAGCUGCAGAAGCUGGGACACCUUGGGCCGCACAGGAAGAUGCGGAUUCCACUUUGGGCAUGGAGGCCCUCAGUCUCCCUGAGCCGGCCUCUGGUGCUGGGGAGGAAAUAGCAGAAGCCCUUUCUAGGCCUGGACGGGAAGCAUGUCUGGAAGCGCGAGCGCACACAGGUGAUGGGGCUAAGCCUGACUCACCCCAAAAGGAGACCCUGGAGGUUGAGAACCAGCAGGAAGGAGGCCUGAAGCCACUGGCACAGGAACAUGGACCCAGGUCAGCACUUGGAGGUGCAAGGGAGGUCCCCGAUGCGCCUCCUGCUGCCUGCCCUGAGGUCAGCCAGGCCCGGCUCCUGAGCCCAGCCAGGGAGGAAAGAGGCCUGAGUGGCAAGUCCACCCCGGAGCCCACGCUUCCCUCAGCUGUGGCCACAGAGGCCAGUCUGGACUCCUGCCCAGAGUCUUCAGUAGGGGCUGUGUCCAGUCUGGACAGAGGCUGCCCUGACGCGCCUGCCCCCACGUCUGCACCAACCUCCCAGCAGCCGGAGCCUGUACUGGGUCUGGGCAGUGUUGAGCAACCCCACGAAGUACCCAGUGUCCUUGGCACCCCCUUGCUGCAGCCCCCAGAAAACCUUGCCAAGGGUCAGCCCAGCACGCCCGUGGACAGGCCCCUGGGCCCUGACCCUUCUGCUCCUGGUACCCUUGCUGGGGCAGCCCUACCCCCACUGGAGCCCCCAGCCCCCUGCCUGUGCCAGGACCCCCAGGAAGACUCUGUGGAAGACGAGGAGCCCCCAGGCUCUCUGGGCCUCCCACCGCCCCAGGCAGGAGUCCAGCCUGCCGCUGCUGCUGUCUCAGGAACCACACAGCCUCUGGGGACUGGGCCGCGAGUCAGCCUCUCGCCUCACUCCCCACUCCUCAGCCCCAAGGUGGCCUCCAUGGAUGCCAAAGACCUGGCCUUGCAGAUCUUGCCGCCUUGCCAAGUGCCUCCUCCCUCUGGGCCCCAGAGCCCAGCUGGCCCUCAAGGGCUCUCAGCCCCCGAGCAGCAAGAGGAUGAGGACAGCCUGGAGGAAGACUCGCCUCGGGCCCUGGGCUCGGGCCAGCAUUCGGAUAGCCACGGGGAGUCAUCAGCCGAGCUGGACGAGCAGGACAUCUUGGCUCCUCAGACCGUGCAGUGUCCAGCCCAGGCCCCAGCAGGCGGCAGUGAGGAGACCAUCGCCAAAGCCAAGCAGAGUCGCAGUGAGAAGAAGGCCCGAAAGGCAAUGUCAAAGCUGGGCUUGCGGCAGAUUCAGGGAGUCACCAGGAUCACCAUCCAGAAGUCCAAGAACAUCCUCUUUGUCAUCGCCAAGCCUGAUGUCUUCAAGAGCCCAGCCUCAGACACUUAUGUGGUCUUUGGCGAGGCCAAGAUUGAGGACCUGUCCCAGCAAGUGCACAAAGCCGCAGCUGAGAAGUUUAAGGUGCCCUCAGAGCCCUCAGCCUUGGUCCCUGAGUCAGCACCCAGGCCCCGGGUGAGGCUGGAGUGCAAGGAAGAGGAAGAGGAGGAGGAGGAAGAGGUGGACGAGGCGGGGCUGGAACUGCGUGACAUUGAGCUGGUGAUGGCGCAGGCCAAUGUGUCCAGGGCCAAGGCCGUGCGGGCUCUGAGAGACAACCACAGUGACAUCGUCAACGCCAUCAUGGAACUGACCAUGUAGCCACUGACCGGAAGCUGGAGCCAUCCUACGCCUUCCCUCAGCUCUGCUACUCAAUAAAUCGGUGUCCCUUCA